CUUUUCUGUGUUGGAAGUUUCCUGAUUAUUGAUUCAAUCUCCUUACAUAUUACAGGUCUAUUCAGACUUUGUAUUUCUUCAUGUCAGUUUUGAUAGUUUGUGUGUUUUUAGGAAUUUGUCCAUUUCAUCUAAGUUAUUCAAUGUGUUAGCAUAAAACUAUCCACAGUAUUCUGUUAUAAUCCUUUUUAUUUCUAUGAUGUCAGUAGUAAUUUCCCCACCACUUUCCUUCCUGAUUUUUGUAAUUUGAGUCUUCUUUCUCUCUUCUCCCACACCACCCCUGCCACACACACACACCCACCACCCCGCACCCCCCCACCAUCUCACUCUCUCUCUCUCUCUGGUCAGUCUAACUAAAGUUUUAUCAAUUUUAUAAUAUCCUUUCUGUCAAUUAUAUACUAUCCAACUUUUGUCUUAAGUCUAUUUUUUCUGAUAUUAGAAUAGCCACUCUAGCUCCCUUUUGGUUACAGUUUGCAUGAAAUAUUUUUUUCAUUCUUUCACUUUCUUUUUUUUCUUUUCCUUUUUCUCUCUCUCUUUUUUUAAGAGAUGGUCUUGCUCUGUUUCCCAGGCUGGAGUACAGUGGCAUGAUCAUAGCUCACUGCAGCCUCAUAAUCUUGGGUUCAAUUGAUAUUCCUGCCUCAGCCUCCUGAAGGCCAGGACUACAGGCACACGCCACUAUGCUCAGCUAAUUUUUGUAUUUUUUUAAUAGACAGGGUCUCUCACUAUGUUUUUCAAGCUGGUCUUGACCUCCUGGACUCAAGCAAUCCUCCUGCCUCUGUCUCCCAAAGUACUGGGAUUACAGGCAUGAGCCACCAUAUCUGGGCCAUCCUGUCACUUUCAACCUAUUUGAGUCUCUGAAUCUAAAAUUAGUCUCUUAUAGAGAGCAUAUAGUUGGAUUAUGUUUUCAAUCCAAUCUGCCAGUAUCAGCCCUUUGAUUGGAGAGUUUAAUCCAUUUAAAUUAAUUAACUUAAUUACUGAAAAGAAAGGCUUUCUUUCCUUUUGCCAUUUACUAUUCUUUUUCUGUAUGGCAUAUCUUUUUGUUCCUCUAUUCCUCCAUUACUGCCUUCUUUUAUGUUUAAUAGAUAUUUUCUAGUGAACCAUUUUGAUUCCCUUCUCAUUUCUUUUACUAUACAUAUUUUUAUUUUUCUUUAUUGUUUGCCCUGAGGGUUAUAAUUAACAUUUUAGCUUAUAAUGAUUUAAUUCAAAUUAAUACCAACAUAAUUUCAAUAGUAUGUAAAAUCCUUGCUUCUUUUAGCUUGUAUUUAUAUGUUGUAUGCUCAGCUACAUAGGUUUGUAAUUAUAGAUUAUGCUGUUUUAUGCAGUUUUAUUUUAUGUCAUGUAGGAGUUAGAAAACUAAAAUACAUUAAUACUGACCUUUAUAUUUAUCUGUGUAGUUACCUUUACCUGCUUUCCUUGUUUUUUUCAUGUGGACCCAGGUUACUUUGUAGUGUAUCAAAUCAGGUCAGCUUGCAGGAAUCCCUUUGGCAUGACUUGUAGGGAAGGUAUACUAGCAACAGACACUCAGUUUUUGUAUUUCUGGUAAUGUGUUAAUUUUUCCUUCAUGUUUGAAGGAUAGUUUUGCCAGAUAAAAAAUUAUUAGUUGUCAGGUUUAUUUUUUUUUCAGCAGUUUGAAUAUAUUACCCCAUUGAUUUCUGGCCUCUAUAGUUUCUGAUGAGAUAUCUGCUAUUAAAAAAUCUGCAGCCGGGCAUGGUGGCUCGCACCUGUAAUCCCAAUAAUUUGGGAGGCUGAGGCAGGCGGAUCACCUGAGGUCAGGAGUUUGAGACCAGCCUGGCCAACAUGGUGAAACCUUGUCUCUACUAAAAAUACAAAAAUUAGCCAGGGAUGGUGGCGCGCACCUGUAAUCCCAGCUACUCAGGAGGCUGAGACAGGAGAAUCGCUUGAACUUGGGAGCCAGAGGUUGCAGUGAGCCAAGAUUGAGCCACUGCACUCCAGCCUGGGUGACAGAGUGAGACUCAUCUUAGAAAAAAGAAAAAAAAUCUGCUUAUGGAAUAUUUCUUAUACAAGAUGAGUCACCUCUGUCUUGCUGCUUUCAAGAUUCUCUCUUUGUUUUUGUCUUUUUAUGGUUUGGUUAUACUGUUUCCUGGUUUGGAUGUCUUUGAGUUUCCUGUUUGGAGUUUAUUAAGUUUUUUGGAUGUGUAGAUUUGUGUCUUUUAUCAAAUUUGGGAAGUUUCCAGCCAUUACUUUUGCAAAUAUCGGUUCUUUCCCUUUCUCUCUUCCUCUCCUCUGGGACUCUCAUUAGGUAUAUUUGGUACACUUGAUGGUGUCCCACGGGCCUCUUAGGUUUUGUUACUUUUUCUUCCUUUUUUUUUUUUCCUGCCUCACAGACUGUAUAAUCUCAAUAGGCCCAUCUUCAAGUUAACCUUCUUCUUCCUGCUUGAAUUUUCUGUGGAACUUUUCUAGUGAAUUUUUCAUUGCAGUUAUAUUUUUUAACCCUACAAUAUUUCUAUUUGGCUUUUAAAAAAUAAUUCUUAUCUCUCUAUUAAUAUUCUCCAUUUAGUGAGACAUUGUUCUCAUAGUUUUUUAUAUAUGGUUUCCAUUAGCUCUGUGAGCAUAUAUGAAAGAGUUAAAGUCAAGUAAGUCCAAUCUGGGCUUCUUUAGGGAGAGUGCCUAUAAAUUUCUUUUAUUCCUCUUUGUGAACUUUGUCCUUUUUUGUGUGCUUCACUUUUUUCCAUUGGAAACUGAACAUUUAAAGUACUAUAUUGUGGCAACUCUGGAAAUCAGAGUCUCCCCUCUCCCUAGGGUUUUUUGUUGAUGAUUAUUAUAGUUUUUUGCUGUUGUUGUUUGGUGACUUUUCUAAACUAAUUAUUUUAUAUUUUUUUCGUUCCCCACUUUUAUUAUCCAAUGCAACUAAUUUUGUAAAGUUUGUAUGUUUUGUCAUAUGUGGCUAAUGAAGUCUGUUCCAGUAGAUUAGCUACCAACCAGUGACCUGACAUAGAUUUUCUUAUGCUGCUGUUUUCAGUAACAUCACUUCCCUGUAAUCAUUUAAAAAUAUGAAUUAAAAAGAAGGAUAAUAAUAGUAAUGGAUGCUGAUCUUUUUUCAUACAUGAUGAACUCUGGUCUUGAGGAUUUUUUACAUUUUUCGCGACUCUAUAUUAUUUUGCAUCCUUUUCUGUCUUCCAAUGAGUAUUCUUUGUCAUCUCGUUUCUUAUACUGCUGGGGAACUUCAACUCAGACCACAAAAUGCAACAAAUAUGAUAUAGUAUUUGCAACUUCUAAAUGCAAUGUGCACACUGAUUCCCAAGUAAAAUUUGCCAUUGAUCUAGACCCAUUCUAGACAUGAGGCCAUGCUCCCUUCUUCCAGUGAAGAUGUGGGAACUCAGUCCCAGGCUAGAUUGGUUUGGGAAGAGUGCCAUUGGAUUGACUAAGCACUGUUAAUGUGGCAUAUUCCCUCAGUCCAUACACUUAUAUUUGCCCCAACACCCGAAAUAACCUGAGGGAAGAAGUCUUUUCACAUUCUGUUUUUGGGCUGUCCUCUGGUACAUGUGACUGGCAGUGACAACCUGCUUUAAAGAGACCUCCUGAGCACUGACCAUGAAGAUGAAAUAUUAGUAAAUGCUAUUCUAGUUAUAUAUAAUCUAGAAAUAAAAUGUCUGGUAAAAGUAAACCACCUCUGGCUGAAGCCAUGAAGUAAUAAAGAAGCUCAGCCUUGAUAGGAAUUAUGUUUCACAAACCCCAGGGGAUGAAAUUUUUCCAAAGAAAUCUCAGAAUUUAGUGGGGAAUGCUCAUUUAUCCUGCCUUCUGCCAGCCCUUUGAAAAACAGGAAACUUCUUGGAUUAAGAAUUUUUUUCUAAUAACAAGUAAAAUAUUUAUGAUAUGAGGCUUAUAUAUUGUUACCAAGCAUUUGCUGACACUGCGUAUAGUUUUAGAUCGUUCUAUUUCCUGAACACAUGAAGGAAAGCAAUAUGGUAAAAUACACAAAUGCAACCCAAAGUAUAGUCUUCCCUCACUGGGGAAAUCCCUUGGAAGUACCCCUUAGCUCAUAUUGCCCCUCAGCGAAUAAUUAUUGAACAGCUUCUAUAAGCUGUGCUUUCUGCUGGAUUGUAUCAGACUUGUACCAAAAUAAGGUGCAAAUGACCAGUAUUAUAGUCUUUCUGUGGGAUAUUUGAAUUUUCAUUUGAGUUUAUUAAAACAUAUUUUAAUGAGAAGUGUGAAUACUUUUUUGCUUUUUGAAAUAGGAUCUUGCUCCGAUACCCAGGCUGGAGUGCAGUGGCACAAUCAUGGCUCACUGCAACCUCGAACUCCGAAGCUCAAGCAAUCCUCCCACCUCAGCCUCCCAAGUAGCUGGGACUACAGGCAUGUGCCACCACGUCCAGUUAAUUUUUUAAAUUUUUUUCUAGAGACAGAGCUUUGCUGUGGUUCCCCGGCUGGUCUCAAACCCCUGGCCUCAAGUGAUCCUCCCACCUUGGCCUUCCAAAGUGCUGGGAUUACAGGUGUGAGCCACUGCACCCAGCUGAGAAAUGUUUUUGAGCAGAGAAUGCAUACAAGAAAUUUCCAGUUAAUGUUUCAAGCCUAUUCCUAAAAGGCCUGCAGAGGAGCAAAGUACAUGAAAUUACAGCCUUAUAUGACAAAAAAAAAAGUGUCUUUAUAUGACAAAAAAAAAGUGUCUUUCUAAACCUCUUACUAUGUACCUACUUGAAACUAUGAUAAAUAUGAAAUUUAAAAUUAUCUUGGACAUGGUUUGAAUGACUUUUAUCUGAAUUUGGUUCACCAGAAAAGGUUUUUUCCAAAACACAUGUAGUAUGAGCAAGCUGAGUGCUUUAUUCCUAGGAGAAUCUUCUCCAGAAAGCACUAUGUAACAUAGUGAGUCUUAAUGAGGAAGGAGGUGUCCCUUGGUUGGUCUUACACAUGCCACCCGAAUCAUGGCUAAGAGCCUCCUCUCAUUUAUUCAUUCAGUAGUGUUAUUGAAUACCUACUAAAUGUAUGGUAUUAUCUAGGCUCUGGGUGGGAGAGUUCCUGGGCUUAGGAAUUUAAAAUCUUUUAUUUCAUAAAUUGGGUAUAAAUAAAAGUGAUUUGGUGACUGCCUUCACUUUGUGAAAAUCCAUCAAGCUGCAUUAAGAUUUAUGCCCUUUUCUGUAUUGUGUUAUAUGUCAAGAAAAAGUUCCUCCUAAAAGUGCUUUGGGAAUUGAAAACUGGAAGACAUUAUUUCCAGCUGAGAAAACAAGGUGAUGGAAUUUUACUGCCAGUCCUGUGAGACUGCCAUGUGUCGGGAGUGCACGGAGGGGGAGCACGCAGAGCACCCCACAGUUCCACUCAAGGAUGUGGUGGAACAGCACAAGGCCUCGCUCCAGGUCCAGCUGGAUGCUGUCAACAAAAGGCUCCCAGAAAUAGAUUCUGCUCUUCAGUUCAUCUCUGAAAUCAUUCAUCAGUUAACCAACCAAAAGGCCAGCAUCGUGGAUGACAUUCAUUCCACCUUUGAUGAGCUCCAGAAGACUUUAAAUGUGCGCAAGAGUGUGCUGCUUAUGGAAUUGGAGGUCAACUAUGGCCUCAAACACAAAGUCCUCCAGUCGCAGCUGGAUACUCUGCUCCAGGGGCAGGAGAGCAUUAAGAGCUGCAGCAACUUCACAGCGCAGGCCCUCAACCAUGGCACGGAGACCGAGGUCCUACUGGUGAAGAAGCAGAUGAGCGAGAAGCUGAACGAGCUGGCCGACCAGGACUUCCCCUUGCACCCGCGGGAGAACGACCAGCUGGAUUUCAUCGUGGAAACCGAGGGGCUGAAGAAGUCCAUCCACAACCUCGGGACGAUCUUAACCACCAACGCCGUUGCCUCAGAGACAGUGGCCACGGGCGAGGGGCUGCGGCAGACCAUCAUCGGGCAGCCCAUGUCCGUCACCAUCACCACCAAGGACAAAGACGGUGAGCUGUGCAAAACCGGCAACGCCUACCUCACCGCCGAACUGAGCACCCCCGACGGGAGCGUGGCAGACGGGGAGAUCCUGGACAACAAGAACGGCACCUAUGAGUUUUUGUACACUGUCCAGAAGGAAGGGGACUUUACCCUGUCUCUGAGACUCUAUGACCAGCACAUCCGAGGCAGCCCGUUUAAGCUGAAAGUGAUCCGAUCCGCUGAUGUGUCUCCCACCACAGAAGGCGUGAAGAGGCGCGUUAAGUCCCCGGGGAGCGGCCACGUCAAGCAGAAAGCUGUGAAAAGACCCGCAAGCAUGUACAGCACUGGAAAACGAAAAGAGAAUCCCAUCGAAGACGAUUUGAUCUUUCGAGUGGGUACCAAAGGAAGAAAUAAAGGAGAGUUUACAAAUCUUCAGGGGGUAGCUGCAUCUACAAAUGGAAAGAUAUUAAUUGCAGACAGUAACAACCAAUGUGUGCAGAUAUUUUCCAAUGAUGGCCAGUUCAAAAGUCGUUUUGGCAUACGGGGACGCUCUCCGGGGCAGCUGCAGCGGCCCACAGGAGUGGCUGUACAUCCCAGUGGGGACAUAAUCAUUGCCGAUUAUGAUAAUAAAUGGGUCAGCAUUUUCUCCUCCGAUGGGAAAUUUAAGACAAAAAUUGGAUCAGGAAAGCUGAUGGGACCCAAAGGAGUUUCUGUGGACCGCAAUGGGCACAUUAUUGUUGUGGACAACAAGGCGUGCUGCGUGUUUAUCUUCCAGCCAAACGGGAAAAUAGUCACCAGGUUUGGUAGCCGAGGAAAUGGGGACAGGCAGUUUGCAGGUACACUCGAUGGUCCCCAUUUUGCAGCUGUAAAUAGCAAUAAUGAGAUUAUUAUUACAGAUUUCCAUAAUCAUUCUGUCAAGGUGUUUAAUCAGGAAGGAGAAUUCAUGUUGAAGUUUGGCUCAAAUGGAGAAGGAAAUGGGCAGUUUAAUGCUCCAACAGGUGUAGCAGUGGAUUCAAAUGGAAACAUCAUUGUGGCCGACUGGGGAAACAGCAGGAUCCAGGUUUUUGAUGGGAGUGGAUCAUUUUUGUCCUACAUUAACACAUCUGCUGACCCACUCUAUGGCCCCCAAGGCCUGGCCCUAACUUCAGAUGGUCAUGUUGUGGUUGCAGACUCUGGAAAUCACUGUUUCAAAGUCUAUCGAUACUUACAGUAAUGGUGGGCAGGUGGAUACCCGCUUCCAUGGUCUUGCACUAUAAACUGGAAUGGAUUUCUCAAUGCGGGACCAGAUUAUGACUAGAGUUUUUAUGCCAGAAGGAAUCAUUGGUGAACUUUCCAAGGUUAUUUCUGAAUGUAACAAUUUCCUUAAAAAUGACUUAUCCAAUUUCUGUAUUUCACCUUUAGGGUUAAAAAAAACUCUUCUACUGAAUCUAUAAAAACUGCAGUUUUACAUCUGUGAACUAUGGCUUAAGGGACAGGAUUUAUGUAGCUAAACUAAUUUUGCAAAUCAAACAGACACUUAAAAAACUAGCAUAUGUAAAGGUAUUCGUUAAUCCUGUGAAUGGUAGCUUUUGCACAGAACUUCCAAAAGCAAAACAAAAACAAAAUCUAUUGUAGUUAUAUACUUCAUUUAACCUAGGUCACAAGACCCAGGGAAUCUUCUAACCUCACUUUUACAGUAGGUAUUACUCUUGUGACAUUUUUUUGGUUAUCAACAACUAAAUAUAAAUUACUUUGGAAAAAGUAAGGCUGUCUUGCAAAAUGAUCCCAGCUCUGAUUAGCAGCCCUCUGGAGUUCAGAACUUAAGUAUCAGUGCAAAUUUCUCAACCUUUCUGGGUUAGACAAAGAUCCUUUUUUGUGUGUUCUUUUCACCACCCCUUUGGCUCACCUUGUAUCAGCAAACAAAGUACUUCUUCAGGGAAACCUGAAAUUUCUAAUGCCUUGAAAAGCAUAUUACAAAAGUAAUGCUACCUUUUGGGAAACAAACUGCCCCGUUAACUCCAGAUCAUUGCACUGGAAUGUAAUCAAGAAAGUUAGUCAUGUUUUAUGUACCAUGUUUUCACACGUGUCUCUUCUCUUCGACUUCCUGAAAGCGAAAGCUUUACCUCCUGCAAAUGUCAGCACAUGUAGUAGGACACCAGUAUCCUAGGACAGAGAGCCAUAAGUAGCCCUUUGGAGGACUGAUGGUGUCAACCAAAGGCAUGUGAUUGAUUAAUGAUUCCCCCUUAGAAAGCAAGUGUUACCAAAGUUGUGUUAUCUUGAAAGCAUUACAGGUAAGGGCAUGUUAUGGUUAUUUAUCAUUGUUUAAUGAAUAGUAGAGGUGUCAAGGGACUAUGUAUACAUGAUUAGGGUAAGAUAGAAUGUAUUAUAUAUAUAUAUAUAUACACACACACAUAUAUAUAGCUGAAUCUUUGGUGUAUUGAAAUAGGCAGCACUCUGAAAGACAGAAGCUUCGUCCAGCCACUCUUCAGCACAUUCCUUUACUAAGCAGUUUAAAGCCGUCCUAGUGGAGCAAGCCCUAAAGCAGAUUUAAUUUUUGCCAUUUUCCAAGAAUGACGGUGGUGGCUUUUAGUCAGAAAAUGGCCUUCUGUGCUUUCAAAAAAAAAAACAAAAAAAAAACCACACACACACAUAAAAAACCCAACAGGUCAAAAUAAAAGUUGAACUUGAGUUACAUUUAAUUUAAAUAUAAAUGCAUUUUGAGAAAUGUUAAGAACAAUUUAGUCAAUCGUUCAUCUGUCAUUGGUACUGUAAAAUAAGCUGUGGUCUAUUUCCACUGUUUAAUUUUCUACUCAGUUCUACCAAAUAGGAUGUCAUGUUUGACAUUUUUGAUAGUGACUUUGGGGUCUUCUUCACUGAAAGCACCUUAGAACUGUACUAUAAGAAAACAUUUCCCCUAUGUAUAAUUAUAUGAAUGUGAUGUUUAUUGCUUAUUAAUUUAUAAUUCAGUCAUUCUCUAUAUAGGACUUCUUAAAAUUUAGAAGGGAAAUCUAGCUACUUCAAAUUGUCUGUUAAAUUUAUUAUGCCCAAAUCAACCUCUGAAAAAAGGUUUUUCCAGGAAGAUUUACAUUUAGGUUUAAUAUUUUUUUAGUUAGGUAGAGUUUUAAAAAAUACUUGAGCCUGUCCGUGAUAAAGCUAUAAAAUUCAAUAACUUUUUAGAAUGUUAAAUGAAGACACUGUUUCCUAACAUCAGUGAGAUACAUCUUUGAAUUUAAACAUUCAUAUUUACUGAGUACCUACUAGGUACCAAGUACUCUUUUAGGCACUGGAAAUACAGUGAUGGACAAAACAGGUAAAAAAUCGCUGCCCCCUCAGAGCUGACAUUCUGGGGUGGGAAUUUCAUUUUGCCACGUACUAACGUUCUGCACAAAAGACAGGCUAGACUCUUGUCUAGAUUGUUUAAAAGAAACUUUUCAAAUUGGUUACAUUAAUUUUAGUUUAUUUUCACAAGUAAAAAUGGCUUUUUAUUUAGAUUCUUUCUGUCCCAGGCUGUUGAUCUUAAAACUAGUUGAUUUAAAGAGUUUUUUUGCACAACAUUUCAAUUAUAUUUGUGAACUUAGAAAUUAACUUACAAUCUAACCAGCCAUCAUAUCAUAUCCUAUCAGGCUAGAUAUCUCAAUAGUAGACUGAAUACAAAGCUAAUUUUUUUUACAUGUCAAUAUUGGCACAAACUGGAAUGAAAGAAUAGUUUGAUUCAGACCUGCUCCACUAUGUGUUGCUAAAACACAUGCUAUGAGCACUCCAGGAAACACUAUAUUUUUUCCAAAAAAUAUGUGAUUAUAUAUGUUAAAGUAUAGAUAACAUUUCACACUUGGAUACAUAUGUGCAUUUACUGUAUUUCUUGGUAAGCAUAUUUUUGGGGGAAAGUGCUGCUGAUAUGAUACAAGUAGACAAAAUUUAAAUGAAAUUUUGUCACAUUCUAUGGAAAAUGGUUUCUGGUAAACUGAGAAGGAUAUUAAAAUAAGUGGCUUUUUUCUGGGCUACCAUUAUUGUUUGAUUUCUCUUUGUCAAGUGUAUAGAACCUGUCAUACAUUCAUGAUAAGUAGCACUGAAAAAUUACUCAUUCAAAUUUCCCCUGGGCACGUAAGGCAAAAUAUUGCCGGUUGGGAUUUCAAGGUCAGUGACGACGCAUUUCCUCCCAGUACAGACCCCCCAGCCCCCCUUGCUGGACAUGGGGAGGCAGAGAGUCACUUGACCAUCCAGAAAUACAUGACUACAAGUCCUUUAUGACUGUUUGCCAUUUUUUUUAAUGGUACUUAGUAUUUUGAUCAAACUUUAGUCUCCAGAACUAAACAAGUCCCUAAGUUUCCUUAUUUUAAUUUACUGUGACUAGAUUUGAAGCAAAUAAAUACUCCAGAUCCAUGCAGCUAGAACACACUUGCUUCCACUACUAAAUAUACAGGGUAUGUCCUAACAUGGAGUUAACUGGAAUAGCAGUACACUAGCAAGUAUCUGUGAAUCCUUAGCACUGACGGGUUAACAGAAAUGCUUUGGUAAUACCUACUUAGUUAAUUGGAGGAAGUAGUAAAUAAACAUUAGGUAAUCUGCAGAUUACUUCAAAUGGGAAAAAUCUUUUUGUAGACUCUAUAGUACCCUCUCUAUUCACUAGCUUCUGAAAAGGGAGGAGUAUUUUUAGUUUGACAAUUUAAUAAUUUAAAAACAAGACAUCUCCAGGUAGGAAAAAAUGAAAGCUAUUUCAUGCAAACAUUAUCUAAUUUAGCUUAAAAGUGAAAGUGGUAAUACUGUUGGUUUCUGUAAAUGUUGCAGGGUUUUAAACUUUAUAAUUACUUUAAUAUUUUUGAUAACUAGAAAUCUAGUAUUGCCAUAAAGGAAACUAAGUGCCCAUCAAAGAUUUGUUUGGUAUAAAUAAAGAAUUAUUUGUUUUGUUUUCAAUGACAGUAAGCUACAAAUCAUGAUGCUUAAAAACUUUCUAAAGAUGAAUUGUGUGGCAGUGAUUGGUCUGUUUGUGGAGAAUGUAUGAAAGCUAUUAAUAUUCUAGAAUAGAUUAAUAAAUUGGCUAUGUUGUUCCAAUGAAUGUACAGCACUUCCAUUAACUUUUGAAAGCAACACAGCCUUAAACUCAAUGCUUUUGCUUUAUGACAUGGGAAUGUUCUGUCAUCAAUGGAGUGUAUUCUUGUAAUAGAAUUCUUUAUAUCGUUCUCAAUUCUAUAGACUUUCAAGCCUAUGUAUGAAUAUGAAGGGGUUUUUUUUUUUUGCUUUGUUUUCUUUUUAGAUUUUGUACAUUCCAUCUUUAUAGGUCUGUUUCAUAUGUUUUAUGUAUAGAACACUAAGUCUUGCACUCUCUGACAUUGAUACUGAUAUAUUCUCGUCAUUUGUUCUUUUAUGAAUCAAAAUGUUGACUGCCUAUUUAAAGAAAAGAAUGAACGCUGUGCAUCAAAGUGUUUGUAUGUUCGUAGCUACAUACGUACCACAGUAUUUUGGAUGCUUUAGUCUACAAUGAAACUUUCAAUUAAUUCUGUCUUGAAACAUAGGAGAAACAGGAUUCAUGUGUAUCUCUUUACCAUGCACAAAAUCUCAAAUCAUUAUAAUAAAGCUUGUUUUCUCCA